ACAUUCCAAUCAUUCACGGAAUAGGAUCGACUCCAUAAUGACUGUGAUGCUGGAAAAAAUUUACUAAAUAUGUACUUACAGAAAAGGGUGACUGCUCAUAAAAUACCUCAGGCAAGCGAUCCCUUAAAACUGAUUGUCCCAACUCAGAGGCCCUCAUUUUCUGCAAUGGUGAUUAUCGGACCAAGAGGCCCGGGAUCCCAGCGUCUGCUGCUCUCGCUUCUGCUCCUUGCAGCCUGGGAGGUGGGGAGCGGCCAGCUCCACUACUCCGUCUACGAGGAGGCCAAACACGGCACCUUCGUGGGCCGCAUCGCUCAGGACCUGGGGCUGGAGCUGGCGGAGCUGGUGCCGCGCCUGUUCCGGGUGGCGUCCAAAAGACACGGGGACCUUCUGGAGGUAAAUCUGCAGAAUGGCAUUUUGUUUGUGAAUUCUCGGAUCGACCGCGAGAAGCUGUGCGGGCGGAGCGCGGAGUGCAGUAUCCACCUGGAGGUGAUCGUGGACAGGCCGCUGCAGGUUUUCCAUGUGGACGUGGAGGUGAAGGACAUUAACGACAACCCGCCGGUGUUCAGAGAAAGGGAACAAAAGGUACCUGUUUCUGAAUCUGCGCCUCUGGACUCUCAUUUUCCUCUAGAGGGCGCUUCUGAUGCGGAUAUCGGCGUAAACUCUCUUUUGACCUAUGCGUUAAGUCUAAAUGAGAAUUUUGAGCUUAAAAUAAAAACAAAAAAAGAUAAAAGUAUAUUGCCUGAAUUAGUUCUUCGGAAGUUAUUGGACAGAGAGCAAACGCCAAAACUCAAUUUAUUGCUGAUGGUAAUCGAUGGCGGUAAACCAGAACUAACAGGGUCUGUCCAGAUUCAAAUAACCGUCCUGGAUGUGAAUGACAAUGGUCCGGCGUUUGAUAAGCCCAGCUAUAAAGUAGUGUUGUCUGAAAAUGUCCAAAACGACACAAGAGUGAUCCAACUAAAUGCUUCCGAUCCAGACGAAGGACUUAAUGGAGAAAUUUCCUAUGGGAUCAAAAUGAUUUUGCCAGUGAGUGAGAAAUGUAUGUUUUCAAUAAAUCCAGACACAGGUGAAAUUAGAAUUUAUGGUGAACUGGAUUUUGAAGAGAAUAAUGCCUAUGAAAUUCAGGUUAACGCCAUUGAUAAAGGGAUUCCUUCCAUGGCAGGUCACAGCAUGGUCCUGGUGGAAGUUCUGGACGUGAAUGACAAUGUCCCUGAAGUAAUGGUUACUUCACUGUCGCUCCCUGUGCAAGAGGAUGCUCAGGUGGGUACCGUCAUUGCCCUGAUUAGCGUGUCGGAUCGUGACUCUGGAGCCAAUGGACAGGUCAUCUGCUCACUGACACCUCAUGUUCCCUUCAAGCUGGUGUCCACCUACAAGAAUUACUACUCGUUGGUGCUGGACAGCGCCCUGGACCGCGAGAGCGUGUCGGCCUAUGAGCUGGUGGUGACUGCGCGGGAUGGGGGCUCGCCUUCGCUGUGGGCCACGGCUAGAGUGUCCGUGGAGGUGGCCGACGUGAACGACAAUGCGCCUGCGUUCGCGCAGCCCGAGUACACAGUGUUCGUGAAGGAGAACAACCCGCCGGGCUGCCACAUCUUCACGGUGUCGGCAUGGGACGCGGACGCGCAGAAGAACGCGCUGGUGUCCUACUCGCUGGUGGAGCGGCGGGUGGGCGAGCACGCACUGUCGAGCUACGUGUCGGUGCACGCGGAGAGCGGCAAGGUGUACGCGCUGCAGCCGCUAGACCACGAGGAGCUGGAGCUGCUGCAGUUCCAGGUGAGCGCGCGCGACGCCGGCGUGCCGCCUCUGGGCAGCAACGUGACGCUGCAGGUGUUCGUGCUGGACGAGAACGACAACGCGCCGGCACUGCUGGCGACUCCGGCUGGCAGCGCAGGAGGCGCAGUUAGCGAGUUGGUACCGCGGUCGGUGGGUGCGGGCCACGUGGUGGCGAAAGUGCGCGCGGUGGACGCUGACUCCGGCUAUAACGCUUGGCUGUCCUACGAGUUGCAACCGGCGGCGGUCGGCGCGCACAUCCCGUUCCACGUGGGGCUGUACACUGGCGAGAUCAGCACGACACGCAUCCUGGAUGAGGCGGACGCUCCGCGCCACCGCCUGCUGGUGCUGGUGAAGGACCACGGUGAGCCCGCGCUGACGUCCACGGCCACGGUGCUGGUGUCGCUGGUGGAGAACGGCCAGGCCCCAAAGACGUCGUCGCGGGCCUCAGUGGGCGCUGUGGAUCCCGAAGCGGCUCUGGUGGAUAUUAACGUGUACCUCAUCAUCGCCAUCUGUGCGGUGUCCAGCCUGCUGGUGCUCACGCUGCUGCUGUACACUGCGCUGCGUUGCUCAGCGCCGCCCACCGUGAGCCGGUGCGCGCCGGGCAAGCCCACGCUGGUGUGCUCCAGCGCCGUGGGGAGUUGGUCUUACUCGCAGCAGAGGAGGCAGAGGGUGUGCUCUGCAGAGAGCCCGCCCAAGACGGACCUCAUGGCCUUCAGCCCAAGCCUUCAGCUGUCUCGAGAAGAUUGUUUAAAUCCUCCCAGUGAACCACGACAGCCCAACCCUGACUGGCGUUACUCUGCCUCCCUGAGAGCAGGCAUGCACAGCUCUGUGCACCUAGAGGAGGCUGGCAUUCUACGGGCUGGUCCAGGAGGGCCUGAUCAGCAGUGGCCAACAGUAUCCAGUGCAACACCAGAACCAGAGGCAGGAGAAGUGUCCCCUCCAGUCGGUGCGGGUGUCAACAGCAACAGCUGGACCUUUAAAUACGGACCAGGCAACCCCAAACAAUCCGGUCCCGGUGAGUUGCCCGACAAAUUCAUUAUCCCAGGAUCUCCUGCAAUCAUCUCCAUCCGGCAGGAGCCUACUAACAGCCAAAUUGACAAAAGUGACUUCAUAACCUUCGGCAAAAAGGAGGAGACCAAGAAAAAGAAGAAAAAGAAGAAGGGUAACAAGACCCAGGAGAAAAAAGAGAAAGGGAACAGCACGACUGACAACAGUGACCAGUGAGGUCCUCAAAUGGAAACAAGCCACUUAGCCAGUUUUUGUAAUAAUGGCAAAUCUCUCCCAUGUAGCAAUUCCCUGCUCCUUUUUCCUAUCUACAUGAGCCCUCUUAGAGACCUCAGAAAUCUGCAGAAAGUUCCCUGUGUCUGUCUAGAACGCAUUUAACAGGUUUUGUCGUAAAAGCUUUACUAAGUCUGGUGUUAACUCUUUCUCUCCACUCUGGCUUGUUUUCAGAACCUAAAAAGCAGACCCAAGUUUCCUUUCUCCUCCGCCGCAAAGGAGAGGCUUCCCAGCCCCGCCAGUGAGAGGUUGGACUCUCUGCCCUGUGCUCCGGGGAUCCUGUCUUGAUGACACUUGCAGGGCAGGCUGAAAAGUUUUGAGAUUGAGCAGCUUGGGAGUUUGUGGCCACUGGGUAUGUGUGGCUACCGCGGGUAUGCGAGUGCCAGAUAUUGGCUGAGACGAGCCAGCUUAGACUAAUUGGUACAAGGAAGGCAAGAAAACAAAGACAAAUAAACAGCGGAAGUUAUCAGUAUGGAGGGGAAGUGUAAACUUAAAGGGACCAGACUUUCUAAAUCUUACAACUCAAGAGGUGGCAGCCACCCUCUAGGAGACAAAACUACCCCCACUGACAAGGCUUUAGGAGACCCUAAAGUCUGUUGGCUGUGACGUCAUUAUACCUAAAAUCUGCAUCAUACCUGCAAGCCAACAGUUCAGUGUUUUAACAGAGAACCACCCUGGGAAACAGAAGCAGAUCUGAUGUGUUUCCUAUACAUGUCCUGUGCUCACUUUAUUAAAAAUUCUUUUGCACACAAUGUUUAUGAAAAGGCCAGAUCCUUUUCCAAUACUUAUGCAAAAGCAAAAGAAAACCCCGACACCUCACCUUUCGCUGUUUGUUGUUUCAUAGAUUUAUUUAAAAAAAGAGAAAGUCUAUAGCUAUAAAUCUUUAAAGAGAAAUAUGAAUACAAUUCCCCUAAACUCUCCUCAAAAGAGAAUUCAGUCUACAGCCAUUUAAAUGAUCAUUGCUGCUACAGAAGUGCUUUAAGAGAAUUGCCUGAAACAUCUGUAUUAUAUCGGCCACCUGCCAAUCACAGCUUUACUCUUUCAGGUCACUCUGGGGCUGCCUCUUGCAUGUAUUACUAAAUAAAAUGAUCUCUCUUUCUCUCUCUCUCUCUCUUUUCUAAGAAACAAUUAUGUGCACUUUGAUACACAACCUUCUCUAACCAACUAUAUAUCAAGACCCAAAAAUUGAAGAAAAAUAUUGUUUUCUCAUACAGUGAGCAGAUUUUUCAAUCUACUAAUUCUGUGACUUGUCUUGGUGUGCUAGCCUACACCUUCUCUUUGGUUUAGUUUUCCUUUUCUAUAACACUCUGAAUUGCUAAUCUUACUAACACCUAUGAUGUUACCUGAAAUCAAUCUCCCAUAUGUAUGCUGUAUGCUAUGCUAAGACUCCUGAAAUAUACUUACUCUGUGCUUGUGUAUGUGAAUGUUAAUGCAACUAUUACCUAGAGUGAACUUUAAGCUUUAUUGUUGAAUGUAAUUCCAUUAUAUUUCCUUUUGUACACCUGUGAAAAAGUGGAGUAGUGUUUUUUUAACCAUUGUUAAUCAGCUUUUGUGUAUGAAAGACACAGUAAAAUUUCUUUCUUAAAUCAAGAUACUGGUGAUUCAAGGAAUUUUAUUUAUGGUCCAGCCAAGAGCCAUCUCGUGCCAAGACUUCUGCUGGCAAGGGAAUGGAUAAAGCUGUUUUGUUCUAGUAACAAUUUUGGAAUGAAUACUGACAAUAUUCCAUGAGGGUGUGCAAGCACAAAUUUUACCAAUCUGACCUCUUUGAAGUUGCAGAAUGCUUUGAAAUUCUAAUGGUAUCUGAAAUAUCAGCUCAUAGAAAGUAACAAAAUUUGCUGUCACCUUAAAUAAGACAUUUUAAUUUUGUUAUAAUGUACAAUUUAGAAGUUUGAUUAAUUAUAUUAUCUAUUUAGGCAUUAAUAUAAAAGAGGUAGGAGUCUGUUAUUUAAAAAAAGCAUUAAAUUUAAAAAAAAACUGUCUUGUCUACUUUUAGCUUCAUUCUCCCAUAUUUUGAAGGGUGUGUAACUUCAGCUCUGCAGGAUUGCAUGGGGUAAAACUUGUUACCAACACAUGUGAACCAUUGCUACAUUGUAGGUUGUGAUCAUUUUGCCCCACUGAAGCCCAUGUAUCUGACCUUACGUGCCUUUUGAACUAGGAGAAUCGGGCUAAUUUAUUAAUGAUGAUAAUUAUAAUGUAUCUGUACAGCACUUUUUACAUUUGCGAAGUGCUUUCCAAUCCAUGUUAGUUACUAGUUAUUACAGCUGUAAGGAUAAAACACGUCAUGUGGAUUCAUUUUGAAUUGGUGCUAUUGGUAUUUCCUCUGUUAUUGCUAAUAAAUGAAAAUGGUGGUAUGAAA